AUGGAGGCAGCCCCGGGGCCGGUGAGGGCCCAGCGGGGCAGGCGGAAGCCGGGCAGGCGUCCGCACCACGAGCAGGGCCGGCCGGGGGUCACUCACGGGGCUGGGCCGGGCGUUCCCUUCUCUGCCUCCGCGUCGUCGCUGUCCCCGUCCUCGGCCGCCGCCGCUUCGGGCUGCUCGUUCGGUCCCCGCGGAGUGGCUCGGACGCUCGGCCCCUCCGUUGUCUUCCGCCCGCUCCUGCUCCCGGCGACGGGCUCCCGCGGCGGCGGCGGCUGCGCGGGCGGACGGCUGCCCAGGGGCUCCCGCGGCUGCCGCCGCGCUGCUGCGCUCGCUUGGGCUGCGGCUGCUGCUGUGGGGCCCGGCGCCGCCUUAGUCUUCGCCUGUGCCCCCGCCCCGGCGCCUGAAGGCUCUGUGUCUCCCAGGCCGCGCCGCUCCCCGAACCCCUCGCCCCGCUUGCGGCCCGAGCCCGGCUUUGACGUGCGCACUGCGCAGCCGCCGAGGACGCGACGUCGGGCGGUGCCGCAACGCCCCCUUCCGCCUCGGGCGCCCCCGAGCGGCCGGCGGACUCAGGGCGCCGCAAGUAGGCGCGAGGCCCGAGCGGGAGGGGCCGCAGAGAAAAGCAGAAGCCAAGCCCCGCAGUUCCUCUUCCUCCGCCGCAGCUUCCAAGGCGGGGCUCAGCCCUUUCUCCUCCGCCUGAGCGCUCUUACUGCGGGAAUCGCACGCCCACUUUCAACGACCACUUCCUCAACUCUUCAAGCUUAAUUCUGCGAGAGGCCGGGAUCCCACUUUGUGCAGACCGAUUCUUACUUUCUUGGAGCAGAUCGCUUCAUUUUAGCAUCCAGGGGGACACAGCAUCCAGGGGGACAAGUGCCAGAACGUUCCAGAUUAAUGGGAAUAUUCCUAUUUAAAUCAGCAACCUGGAUUUAAGUCCUGCUCCACCAUUUGCUAUCUAUGGGCUGUUUCACGUCCCUGUGCCUGGAUUUCCUCACACAUUAAAAAAAAAAGUGUGUAAUAAUAUAGUGGUACCAGCCACGGGCUUCUGAGGAUGAACGGGACAGUGCAUUGCAAAGCUCUGACAACGGAGCCUGGCACAUACAAAUGCCAUAUGUGUGUAUUUUUGUUUCUUUGUUUUUAAUGUGUAACUGAACUACUUUUUAAGCGCCUCCUGUACGUCAGGGAUGGGGCAGUGAGCGAAACAGUCCAUGCUCCUAGCACAAACAGUUGACAAAUAAUUGACUAAUAAACCUACAGCCUGAAUUGGCAUCACCAAGAAUUAACACCCGACUGCCCAAAUCCCUGUCAGGACUGUGGGUUGCCUUGCAGCUGGCCUUUUCUCCCAGAAUCUGAAGGAGUUCUACAAGCUGAGGCUUAGCGAUUUGGCAUAAACCUUGAAAGACUCAGCCCUUCAGGAUACCAUGAAUUCUCCCUGGACAAGCUGCUGCCUGGACCACUAAGGAAGCCCAGCAAAAUGCUCAGGCCAUGUAUGCCCUUUCGUGACAAGUGCCAAGAUUGUGGACAAUAUCACAAGACAUUGACAGCUUUAAGAAACUCAAAAACUGGUGCUGGAAGAUUUUCUUCUGCUAACCUCUUGGAAUUCACUGAACCAGCUAAUUCUCAGAUUCAACUACUGGCUUUUACUUUAAUAAAUGGCAAAGCAGAUGACCGCAAAAGGCCACACUGCCCUCCCAGUUUCUUCCAGAAGACUGGUCUUCAUCCUGCCUCAUGACUCCCAUAGACUCCAGGGUGCCUCCCUCUUUUUUUUUUUGAGACAGAGUCUGGCUCUGUCAUCCAGGCUGGAGUGCAGUGGCGCAAUCUCAGCUCACUGCAACCUCUGCCUCCUGGGUUCAAGCGAUUCUCCUGCCUCAGCCUCCGCAGUAGCUGGGACUACAGGCAUGCACCACCAUGCCUAGCUAAUUUUUUUUUUUUUGUAUUUUUAGUAGAGACGAGGUUUCACCAUGUUGGCCAGGCUAGUUUCAAACUCCUGACCUUAGGUGAUCUGCCCACUUCGGCCUCCCAAAGUGCUGGGAUUACAGGCAUGAGCCACCGCGCCUGGCCAAUGCCUCCCUCUUUUACCUUCGUCUGCAAAAUCCCAGGCCCCCUUCCUUUUCUUUGAGAUGUCCCUCAUUAAUGAGCAUUCUCUUCAUGGCACUAGCUUGAAUAAAACCAUCUCCUUAAUCGUCAAGUGAAUUUCGUCUGUCACAGUGCCAGCGACGAACUCUCAUAAGGGCAGCCAGCACUUCGCCCCUGACUGUCCUGCUGGAGUGACAACCAUCUGUGCUGAGCCUCUUUGCAGUCCUCCUGUGGCUCAUCCCUCGGACAGCCGCCCUUUCAACAUCUCAGGCUGAAGAUCUCUGUGUACAGUCACAAUCUUGGUGCAGCUUCUGCAGACCCUGGUGCAUCCAGUCAUACCAAUUCCACAUCCACAGCACAUGCUACUAGCCACUUCCAGGAUCAUUAAAAUACAUUUCUGGCCAUUUCUGGACCCAGUCCAAAGAUAAAGACUGACUAUGCAACAAACAAAUGACAGAUUAAAGGAGACAAAAAUUACUUUCACAAUGUAUAAUUACCAACAAUGUAACAUUUUAUUAAAUGUGUCUGUAGUCUGCA